GCUUUUCGCUCGCUGCACUCCAAGCCCCGGAACACCCGCGUCCGCACACUAAGGGCACCACCGCUCUCCCACCUCUGCGCUGUCAGAUGUCAGGCGCGGAGGUGCUCUGGGCACCGAGGUGCUGGCGAACCAAACAAGUAUCACCCCGGACGCCUGCCCCCAUUCCGAGAGAGCGGGCGGGAUGGCCACAGGCUGCAAUACAGUGACACGAUCACAGCUCACUGCUACAGCCUCUACCUCCUGGGCUUAAUCCAUCCUCCCUCCUCAGCCUCCCAAGCAGCUGGGACUACAGGUGAUUUUGAUAUGCUGCUAAGGUUUGAUAAGAGAAAUGAGAUUCAGAGAACAGAUUAUAUUGUUGAAGAGCUUGACUGGAAAUGAUCCAAACGGAAACAUUGGCUCUUCCUGGGGUUCCAGCCUGCUGUCUUGACAGGAACUAUACCAUCAGCUCUCCUGGGUCUCUUACAUGCCAAGUCAUCCUGCAGAUCUGGGACUCACUCCGUAAUCAGCUUGAUUGCUGUAAGUUGAACACGUCAGUGGCAUGGGCACCAGCUGCACAACCCUAGGAGCCACCAAACACAGUAUAUUCUAUAUAAAUGUUGCUGCCAGGAGCCCCAGUUCAAACUACAAUAUGGAGUUUUGCUCUUUUUUGCCCAGGCUGGAGUGCGAUGGCACAAUCUUGGCUCACUGCAACCUCCACCUCUUGGGUUCAAGCAAUGCUUCUGCCUCAGCCUCCCAAGUAGCUGGGAUUACAGAGACAGGGUUUCACCAUGUUGGACAGGCCGGGCACCUGACCUCAAGUGAUCUGCCCGCCUCAGCCUGCCAAAACCCUGAGAGAUGGUUGGUGCCAUGUGGAAGGUGAUUGUUUCGCUGGUCCUGUUGAUGCCUGGCCCCUGUGAUGGGCUGUUUCGCUCCCUAUACAGAAGUGUUUCCAUGCCACCUAAGGGAGACUCAGGACAGCCAUUAUUUCUCACCCCUUACAUUGAAGCUGGGAAGAUCCAAAAAGGAAGAGAAUUGAGUUUGGUCGGCCCUUUCCCAGGACUGAACAUGAAGAGUUAUGCCGGCUUCCUCACCGUGAAUAAGACUUACAACAGCAACCUCUUCUUCUGGUUCUUCCCAGCUCAGAUACAGCCAGAAGAUGCCCCAGUAGUUCUCUGGCUACAGGGUGGGCCGGGAGGUUCAUCCAUGUUUGGACUCUUUGUGGAACAUGGGCCUUAUGUUGUCACAAGUAACAUGACCUUGCGUGACAGAGACUUCCCCUGGACCACAACGCUCUCCAUGCUUUACAUUGACAAUCCAGUGGGCACAGGCUUCAGUUUUACUGAUGAUACCCACGGAUAUGCAGUCAAUGAGGACGAUGUAGCACGGGAUUUAUACAGUGCACUAAUUCAGUUUUUCCAGAUAUUUCCUGAAUAUAAAAAUAAUGACUUUUAUGUCACUGGGGAGUCUUAUGCAGGGAAAUAUGUGCCAGCCAUUGCACACCUCAUCCAUUCCCUCAACCCUGUGAGAGAGGUGAAGAUCAACCUGAACGGAAUUGCUAUUGGAGAUGGAUAUUCUGAUCCCGAAUCAAUUAUAGGGGGCUAUGCAGAAUUCCUGUACCAAAUUGGCUUGUUGGAUGAGAAGCAAAAAAAGUACUUCCAGAAGCAGUGCCAUGAAUGCAUAGAACACAUCAGGAAGCAGAACUGGUUUGAGGCCUUUGAAAUACUGGAUAAACUACUAGAUGGCGACUUAACAAGUGAUCCUUCUUACUUCCAGAAUGUUACAGGAUGUAGUAAUUACUAUAACUUUUUGCGGUGCACGGAACCUGAGGAUCAGCUUUACUAUGUGAAAUUUUUGUCACUCCCAGAGGUGAGACAAGCCAUCCACGUGGGGAAUCAGACUUUUAAUGAUGGAACUAUAGUUGAAAAGUACUUGCGAGAAGAUACAGUACAGUCAGUUAAGCCAUGGUUAACUGAAAUCAUGAAUAAUUAUAAGGUUCUGAUCUACAAUGGCCAACUGGACAUCAUCGUGGCAGCUGCCCUGACAGAGCGCUCCUUGAUGGGCAUGGACUGGAAAGGAUCCCAGGAAUACAAGAAGGCAGAAAAAAAAGUUUGGAAGAUCUUUAAAUCUGACAGUGAAGUGGCUGGUUACAUCCGGCAAGCGGGUGACUUCCAUCAGGUAAUUAUUCGAGGUGGAGGACAUAUUUUACCCUAUGACCAGCCUCUGAGAGCUUUUGACAUGAUUAAUCGAUUCAUUUAUGGAAAAGGAUGGGAUCCUUAUGUUGGAUAAACUACCUUCCCAAAAGAGAACAUCAGAGGUUUUCAUUGCUGAAAAGAAAAUCGUAAAAACAGAAAAUGUCAUAGGAAUAAAAAAAUUAUCUUUUCAUAUCUGCAAGAUUUUUUUCAUCAAUAAAAAUUAUCCUUGAAACAAGUGAGCUUUUGUUUUUGGGGGGAGAUGUUUACUACAAAAUUAACAUGAGUACAUGAGUAAGAAUUACAUUAUUUAACUUAAAGGAUGAAAGGUAUGGAUGAUGUGACACUGAGACAAGAUGUAUAAAUGAAAUUUUAGGGUCUUGAAUAGGAAGUUUUAAUUUCUUCUAAGAGUAAGUGAAAAGUGCAGUUGUAACAAACAAAGCUGUAACAUCUUUUUCUGCCAAUAACAGAAGUUUGGCAUGCCGUGAAGGUGUUUGGAAAUAUUAUUGGAUAAGAAUAGCUCAAUUAUCCCAAAUAAAUGGAUGAAGCUAUAAUAGUUUUGGGGAAAAGAUUCUCAAAUGUAUAAAGUCUUAGAACAAAAGAAUUCUUUGAAAUAAAAAUAUUAUAUAUAAAAGUAAUGAUGAGUCAAUUCUUGAUAAGCAGAUGCUCUUAUGCAGAGAACAAACUUAAUCUUUGCCUUUUCAUUUUCUUUUUCCUUCUUUGAGUUUGAGGUGUACACACUUCUGAAAGAGCCUGCAGGCUACAUUAGUUAUAAGAGCCAUUUUAAUUUGGGCUUCAAAUUCUCUACUUCUUUUCCCCAAAUAAAGAACAACCUAAUUUUGUAUCAUUGUUAGAAUAUCAAAAAAAAUUAAGAUAAGCUGGCAUCAAUAUAUACAUUUAUAAAUAUACAUUCAUUAGCAGUUUUCUGACUAAAAUGUCACAUCCUGGCACAUCUUUUCGAUUUAUGCAUCAUGUGCUCACAUCUCUGAAAUUCUACAAGACGUGUGGAUUUUUCCACAUCACUUCCUUCUCAUAUUACCCAUCUAUGAACUGGCUCACUGGAGAAUUAAAUUUAAAAAGUCAAAGCCUGUUCUUGCGGCAAAUAGUUUAUGGAGUUUAUUCUUUUAAUUUCUCAUGUUGUGCCUGAUUACGUUCAGGUUUGUGAUCUUCCUUUUUAAAUUGUUCAUUGUACCCAUGUCCUAGAAGUCAUUAAAUCAAAUAUUCUGAUCAAAA